AAAGGAAGUGCUGGUCACCCUGGAGGUGUACUGGUUUGGGGAAGGUCCCCGGCCCCCACAGCCCUCUGGGGAGCCUCACCCUGGCUCUCCCCACUCACCUCAGCCCUCAGGCAGCCCCUCCACAGGGCCCCUCUCCUGCCUGGACAGCUCUGCUGGUCUCCCCGUCCCCUGGAGAAGAACAAGGCCAUGGGUCGGCCCCUGCUGCUGCCCCUGCUGCUCCUGCUGCAGCCGCCAGCAUUUCUGCAGCCUGGUGGCUCCACAGGAUCUGGUCCAAGCUACCUUUAUGGGGUCACUCAACCAAAACACCUCUCAGCCUCCAUGGGUGGCUCUGUGGAAAUCCCCUUCUCCUUCUAUUACCCCUGGGAGUUAGCCAUAGUUCCCAACGUGAGAAUAUCCUGGAGACGGGGCCACUUCCACGGGCAGUCCUUCUACAGCACAAGGCCGCCUUCCAUUCACAAGGAUUAUGUGAACCGGCUCUUUCUGAACUGGACAGAGGGUCAGGAGAGCGGCUUCCUCAGGAUCUCAAACCUGCGGAAGGAGGACCAGUCUGUGUAUUUCUGCCGAGUCGAGCUGGACACCCGGAGAUCAGGGAGGCAGCAGUUGCAGUCCAUCAAGGGGACCAAACUCACCAUCACCCAGGCUGUCACAACCACCACCACCUGGAGGCCCAGCAGCACAACCACCAUAGCCGGCCUCAGGGUCACAGAAAGCAAAGGGCACUCAGAAUCAUGGCACCUAAGUCUGGACACUGCCAUCAGGGUUGCAUUGGCUGUCGCUGUGCUCAAAACUGUCAUUUUGGGACUGCUGUGCCUCCUCCUCCUGUGGUGGAGGAGAAGGAAAGGCUUGAGCCACCGCACCCGGCCAGUUUGGAAUCUGUUAUACGGGAGAUCCAUGUGUGGCAUCUCAGCAGAGUUGUCCAUUGGAAACUUGGAUGUACACAUUUCCAGUUCAAAAGAGAGGACAAGGCUCCAGGCAGCAAUGAGUUCUACCUCAAUAUCCUCCAAACCUGACAGUAGCAGGGCGCCAAGCAGUGACUUCUGACCAACAGAGUGUGGGGAGAAGGGAUGUGUAUUAGCCCCGGAGGACGUGAUGUGAGACCCGCUUGUGAGUCCUCCACACUCGUUCCCCAUUGGCAAGAUACAUGGAGAGCACCCUGAGGACCUUUAAAAGGCAAAGCCGCAAGGCAGAAGGAGGCUGGGUCCCUGAAUCACCGACUGGAGGAGAGUUACCUACAAGAGCCUUCAUCCAGGAGCAUCCACACUGCAAUGAUAUAGGAAUGAGGUCUGAACUCCACUGAAUUAAACCACUGGCAUUUGGGGGCUGUUUAUUAUAGCAGUGCAAAGAGUUCCUUUAUCCUCCCCAAGGAUGGAAAAAUACAAUUUAUUUUGCUUACCAUACACCCCUUUUCUCCUCGUCCACAUUUUCCAAUCUGUAUGGUGGCUGUCUUCUAUGGCAGAAGGUUUUGGGGAAUAAAUAGCGUGAAAUGCUGCUGACA